GAUGAUGAUGAUGAUGAUGGCAAUAACAAUGAUGACAGUCAACACUGCCGCGUGCCGGGCUCUGGCCCUUUGCAUGUCUGGGCCGGCUGUACAAGGCACUGCUGGGGCUCCCGGGCUGGGAGCCAGGGACAGGCACCGUCACAGCAGCCAAGGGGCCCCCCUACCACCCCAGCACCUGCUGGCCCUGAACCAGCUGCUCCUUGAGAGCUUUGACAGACUCUUCCGCUUGGCAGCAUUUUAAUCUGCUGGUGCAAGAGCCUUGUCGCUUCCUCAAAGCCUGUGCCCAUGGCCGUGGGCAGCUGCCUGUCCCUGUAUAGGCAGAGCUGCGUCAUGCCCUGUGGCCCCAGGAAAAUGGGGACGUCGGGAGCAUUCUCUGGACAGCAGGAGAUGCAUGUCGACAGGCUGGCCCUGCCUCUUCCCACCCCAGAGUGAUGCAGCGGUGUCCUGGACCCCUGGGGAGAGGUGACCCCCCCAGCAGGAAGCUGGGCCUGGUUUCUGUCCCUCUGCAGCCACAAGGCCUGGCUAGGAUGCUGGGAGCACCACACCCUGGAGACUCAGCUCACCAAGGACUCAGGGGCGGGGGCUCCCCUGGCACCUGGGAAGCUGGGCCCCCGGCCCCCUGGACUCCCACCCAGACACCAUCUCAACCCAGGCACUUCCCCCGGGCCAGAGGGCAGCCUGGCAGCCCUGGACUCCGGGAGGGCCGAGUCUGGGGAGCUGGACGACGUCACAUUCCACUCUUGAUGAUGCCGCCCCAGUCCUACAAUCUGGACAGCAGGAGAAGCUGCCCAUUUCCUCCAUCUCCGGUAAUGAGAAGCAAAUGCUGAUCCUGGCCGUCUCCUGGCUCUUGGGUCCCUAGGUUCCUGCUGCCCCUGCCAGUUCCUGGAAGAUGCCAGCAGGAGGGAGGGCAGUGGAGCUGGACUUGCGCCCACAACAGGAUCUGGCCAUAAACGCAGUCAGGGCGAGGCUGCGGGGUGGGUGGCUGAGCCUCCUGGUGGACUAUCUCCCCUCCCACCCCCCGCCCUGGCCCGCAGCUGUUGGCUCUUCCUGGGAAGCCACAGCCUUUGUUUGUUCCUUGAAGGAGCUGGUGCGUUGCCUGCGAGCUCCUCUGCAGGCUUGGGGGUCGCACCUGCUGUCCACCCCCCUCGAAACCAGCUCCAUCCAGCAGCAGGCUGCAAGCCUGGAGAGGCCACCGGGGACCAGGCAGGGAAACUGAGGUCCCAAAAAGGCAGGGAACAGGUGCAGGGGGCCUGUCUGACCUGCGCUGGGACUGGGCCAGGUGAGUCUCCUCCAGGGCCCAGCCCCAUCUUGGACAGAGGAAGUUGAUAGUCAGGAAAGGCAGGAGUGGCCUCUUCUAACAAUUUCAGCUCUGAAGGGGCCAAGGGUGGCGAUGCUGACAGCAUUUCCUCCAGCUCCCACCUGCCUGCUCCGGGGAACUCCCUACCCAGGCAUUGAUAUUCACCUGGUGAUACUAAUAAUUGUCUCAGGUGAUAAAUUGUCUCAGCUGCUCUCCCACAUGGCCCACAGGUCCCUGGAGGUUCCCCGGAUCCUUUCAGGGAAGACCAUGGGCCCUAAACGAUCUUCAUAACAAAACUGAGAAGUGGCCUGGCUUCUUCACUGCGUGCCUGUGUGCUGGGAUCUAGCGUGGCCCGACUGGGCAGCUCCUUUCCUUCCCUGACGCUGCUCCAGGGGAAAGAAGGACCAGGGUCAAUCCGGGGUGCCCCAGGUGGAUCAGCGAAUGCCCCUGAAGCCAGGUGCCAGUUGCAUCCCCGUCAGAUGCCCCCACCCCAGUCUCCUGAGCCUCAUUAGUCACCCCUCAUUUUCCUCUGGGGACCCCAGGCCCCAGCUCCUGUCUGGUUAGAGGCUGAAGGGGUCUGAGCGACACCUACCCUAGGGGACCUCCGGAGGGGUCUUGGUGUCCUCUGACUUCUGUCCUCAGAAGGGAGCUCAGAAUGCAGCUGAGGCUUCCCCUGGGGCCCAGGGUGUCUGUGUCCGAGCCACAGCCAGAGUGUGCCCUGGAGAGUCGCUGGGAUGCACGGUGGGCUCUCGUCAUCCUGUCCCCACUCCAGGCUCAGGCUGGAGCCGUGAUGGCACCGCUGCACUCCAACCUGGGCAACAGAGUGAGACCCUGUCUCUAUAAAAUAAAAACAAAAAUAAAGAAGAGCAUGUGGUUUCUGCAGUUUCCUGGCCAAAAAUGCAUAACUCCAAUCUCAAUCAUAAGAACACAUCCAACGUCCCCAACAAGGGGAGGUUCUACACACACCUGCCCAGAGCCCCUCAAAAGUGUCAAGGUGUGAAAGACAUGGAGGCAUGUAGAAGACGGGAGAGCCAGUGUGGCCUGUGGUAUGUUCAUGACGGUCACAGGUCAGCGCCCACGGUCACUCAGCAGCCAUGCCAGGCAGGCCCCAGGGGCCCAAGAGGAAGGUGGGAUGUGGCGGGAUGGGGGCUCUGCACGGCCCUGCAGCACAAGUGCCCUGCCGACUCCAGGGGCAGCAAUCUGGUCCCCUCAUGGUGCCAUUCCCCAGGGACGGGUCCUCGCCUGCCUCGCCGGCCCUCCACAGACAGGACAGGGACAGGUCGUCAGCUGUCACGGAGGCCCUCGCAGUUUUCUGAAUGUGGACUUGCUGUUCCUGCCCAUGGCUUCGUCCACGGACUCGACAGCACCCCACUGUCCAUCACACCCCCACCGAUGCUGCUUCCCACAGCAGGACUCAUCCCAUGCUCAGGCAGUGCUCCCAGGAGCAGCGGGUUAAUAGAGCGUGGGACGGCCCCUGAAGACCAGUUAUGGCGCCGGCCAGGAGGCCCUCUGAAAGGACGGGCGCAACCCCGCAGAACAGACCAGGUGCUCGCCAUCCAUGUCCGGUGCCGCUUCUCUGUGGCGAUGGUAUCCAGGAAUCACGGGUGGGAGUCACGGCCACAGUCCCUGUCGCACCAGCCGCCUGCCCACACAGCCACCGUUCACUCUAGCUUGAAGGUCCCGCUUCCUCAGGGAGGAGCACUCCCUCCAGGGUCGAGGUGCUGGCCGUGUGGAGUUCGACGUCGGGACUGUCCCCAGGGGCCUCUCUUCCCACUGAAUCGACAGAGAGAAUGUGAGCUUGCUGUCCGGCGGGCGGGGCCGGGGAUCCUGUCCGUCGAGGGGACACCGGAUUGCUGCGGAGAGAGGACUAGACCCAGAGUCCAGCCAAGACCAGAACUGAGACCAGGCGACCAGCAGAGCCUGCACAAUAAUAAUGCUUCGUUUUGCAAAUGUAUUUUGUUCUUUUAUUGUAUAUAUUUAUCAUGUCCAAUGUGAUGUUUUGAAACGUGUUUACAUUGUGCUUAAAUCAAGCAGCAUAACACACAUGACUUCACAUACUUCCCAUUUUUUUGUGGUAAGAACACUCAAAUUCUACUCGCAAUGAUUUUCUUUCUUUUUUUCUCUCUCUUAAUGAUUUUCAAGGAUGCAAUAUGGUGUUAUUAACUGUAGUCACCAUGCUGUGCAGUACAUCUCUUGAAUUUAUUCCUUUUGUCUAACGGAACUUUUUUUUUCUUUUUGAGAUGGAGUUUGCUCUGUCGCCAGGCUGGAGUGCAGUGGCACGAUCUCGGCUUACUGUAACCUCUAUCUCCCAGGUUCAAGCAACUCUCAUGCCUCAGCCUCUGGAGUAGCUGGGAUUACAGGCACCCGCCACCACGCCCAGCUAAUUUUUUUGUUUGUUUGUUUUUUGAACCGGAGUCUCACUCUGUUGCCAGGCUGGAGUGCCGUGGUGCCAUCUUGGCUCACUGCAACCUCCGCCUCCUGGGUUCAAGCGAUUCUCCUGCCUCAGCCUUCUGAGUAGCUGGGAUUACAGGCGCCUGCCACCAUGCCUAGCUAAUUUUUGUAUUUUUAGUAGAGAUGGGGUUUCACCAUGUUGGCCAGGAUGAUCUUGAUCUCCUGACCUCAUGAUCUGACCGCCUCAGCAUCCCAAAGUGCUGGGAUUACAGGCAUGAGCCACCGCGCCUGGCCUAAUUUUUGUAUUUUCAGUAGAGACGGGGGUCUCAUCAUGUUGGCCAGGCUGGUCUCGAACUCCUAACCUCAGGUGAUCUGCCUGCCUCUGCCUCCCAAAGUGCUGGGAUUACAGGCAUGAGCCACUGUGCACGGUCUGUAACAGAAACUUUGUACUCUUGGACCAACCCCUCCCCAGUUCCCAGCCCCUAUGUCCCUGGGUCCUCUCUCUGCUUCUGUGAGUUCAACUUUUCUAGGCUCCACUUAUGUGUGAGAUCAUGCAGUGUCUGUCUUUCUGGGCCUGGCUUCCUUCAUUCAGCAUGAAGUCCUGCAGUUCAUCCAUGUCGGCACCAAUGACACAAUUCCCUCUUCUGUGGAGGAACAGUUCUCUGACGUGGAUGCACCUUCCUUGGCUGCUGGACGCUGAGGCUGGUUCCAUGUCUGGCCGUAGUGGACAGCGCUGCGGCGAACAUGGGGUGCGGGUGUCUCUUCUGCGUACUGAUGUGGCCUCCGCGUGUCACGCCCGGGAGUGGGACAGCUGGAUUACGUGGUGGUUCUGUUUUCAGUUUUUUGGGAAUCUCCAUGCUGUUUUCCAUAACGGCCAUCAUCACAGACUUCUUAUCAUGAAAUCAUUUUAGACUCGUAGAAUCCUGGUAAAAAUAGUAUAGAGAAUGGUGAUCUGUCAUCUCUGGGCAGGGCAAAGGGAGCUGGGGCGACCAGGCAGGAGGGAGGUUUGCUUUCAUGAUCUGUUCUUUACCUAUUCAAAAACAAUUAAAAUAAAGGCCAAGGCAGAUGGA